AAAGGCUCCGCCAGGUCCCCAGCGACCGCCACCCCUCCGGCCGAGCCCAGCUCCCCGCGGCGGCCGCUAGCCCCCGGCCCCGAGCCACCACUCCGACCUAGCGGCCGCCGCCCCCGGUGCGGGAUGAGGAGAUCCGCGGCCGCCACUGGGCCCCAUGGAGGAGCCGCAGCCGCCCCGCCCACCAGCGAGCAUGGCCUUACUGGGCAGCCAGCACUCCGGCGCCCCCUCCGCGGCCGGCCCACCUGGCGGGACUUCCUCCGCGGCCACGGCGGCCGUGCUCUCCUUCAGCACCGUGGCGACCGCGGCGCUGGGGAACCUGAGCGACGCAAGCGGAGGCGGCACAGCUGCCGCUCCCGGUGGCGGCGGCCUUGGCGGGUCCGGGGCAGCGCGGGAGGCGGGGGCGGCGGUGAGGCGGCCGCUAGGCCCGGAGGCGGCGCCGCUGCUGUCGCACGGAGCUGCAGUGGCGGCCCAGGCGCUCGUCCUCCUGCUCAUCUUCCUGCUGUCUAGCCUUGGCAACUGCGCGGUGAUGGGGGUGAUUGUGAAGCACCGGCAGCUCCGCACCGUCACCAACGCCUUCAUCCUGUCGCUGUCCCUAUCGGAUCUGCUCACGGCGCUGCUCUGCCUGCCCGCCGCCUUCCUGGACCUCUUCACUCCGCCCGGGGGUUCGGCGCCUGCCGCCGCCGCGGGGCCCUGGCGCGGCUUCUGCGCCGCCAGCCGCUUCUUCAGCUCGUGCUUCGGCAUCGUGUCCACGCUCAGCGUGGCGCUCAUCUCGUUGGACCGUUACUGCGCUAUCGUGCGGCCGCCGCGGGAGAAGAUCGGCCGCCGCCGCGCGCUGCAGCUGCUGGCGGGCGCCUGGCUGACGGCCCUGGGCUUCUCCUUGCCCUGGGAGCUGCUCGGGGCGCCCCGGGAACUCGCGGCGGCGCAGAGCUUCCACGGCUGCCUCUACCGGACCUCCCCGGACCCCGCGCAGCUGGGCGCGGCCUUCAGCGUGGGGCUGGUGGUGGCCUGCUACCUGCUGCCCUUCCUGCUCAUGUGCUUCUGCCACUACCACAUCUGCAAGACGGUGCGCCUGUCGGACGUGCGCGUGCGGCCGGUGAACACCUACGCGCGCGUGCUGCGCUUCUUCAGCGAGGUGCGCACGGCCACCACCGUCCUCAUCAUGAUCGUCUUCGUCAUCUGCUGCUGGGGGCCCUACUGCUUCCUGGUGCUGCUGGCCGCCGCCCGGCAGGCCCAGACCAUGCAGGCCCCCUCGCUCCUCAGCGUGGUGGCCGUCUGGCUGACCUGGGCCAAUGGGGCCAUCAACCCUGUCAUCUACGCCAUCCGCAAUCCCAACAUUUCGAUGCUCCUAGGGCGCAACCGCGAGGAGGGCUACCGGACUAGGAAUGUGGACGCUUUCCUGCCCAGCCAGGGCCCGGGUCUGCAAGCCAGAAGCCGCAGUCGCCUUCGAAACCGCUAUGCCAACCGGCUGGGGGCCUGCAACAGGAUGUCCUCUUCCAACCCGGCCAGCGGAGUGGCAGGGGACGUGGCCAUGUGGGCCCGCAAAAAUCCAGUUGUACUUUUCUGCCGAGAGGGACCACCAGAGCCGGUGACGGCAGUGACCAAACAGCCUAAAUCCGAAGCUGGGGAUACCAGCCUCUAAGACGGUUGGAAUGGCCAGCUUAUGAAGGCAAAUUUCCACUCGCAUUAUUUAAUGAUGGAAGAUUCUGGGGGAGAGUUGUGGAUUUCAUAAAGCCAAACAUUUAAAGCUAGAGACGGGGGAGGCUUACCACUUUCCCCAAACAACAUAAAAGACAAUGUCCCUUCUUCAAAAGUGCCAAAAGGAAUGUAAAAUGCAAAAAUUAAAACAAUCUUAAACCACAUAACCAAGCAUUGUGAACUGUAAGUGCCAAAAAUGACAAAAAUAACAUUCACUAUAACUGAAAAGCUCAUAUUAUAGGACCACACUGUGAAACAAACAAAACAUUGAAUGCAACCAGUAUUGUUCAACUACACAGAAUUUCAGGAAUGAAUGGAGACCUUCAGAGCUGCUUGAAAGCCCCUCUAAAUCGCUACCAUCCAACAAAACUUUAGCUUCUAGAGCUUGCACCUCUGACAUGCUUUGGGUGCUUAGAUUGCAAGUGGAAAAGUCUUAUCCUUACACACAUUGGUGCACCUCCUCACCCCACCCCCUAAUAACCUUUGUGGAAAAUUUUUAAUUCAUAACCCAUUUAAAAUCAUUUUAGGAUUUUGAAAAGCUGGUUAUUAUUAGAUAAAAUUCAACCAUCUGAAGGACAAAUAGAAGUAUGAACAUAAAGAAAUGUGUCUUUUAAAUGUUUUCCAAGAUUAUAUGUAAAAAUUAACAUUCCUUCCACCCGCGUCAUACCUCCAAAAUGAUCUUCCUUGGAAAACUUUGAAGUUUUAUCCUUACUCUAACCUGUUACUUUUAUUUCUGAUAAAUUUUGGAAUGCUGCUCUCAGAAUGCUUUCACAUUUAAAAAAAUAUUUUCAUUGUAGAAAAUUUUUGUCUUUUGAGGUAAAUUUGAUUUUUGGAUAUAGCCAAAAAUGUAAUUUGAAGUCAAGUUGAUUGAAUAAGGUGAGUGAUGCCACUUUAUUUAAAUUUUUAUUAUUUUUUAAAAUGAGACCUCUAUAAAACAACAAGGUUGGGUUUCCUACGUGGCUUUUAGCUAACUGAAAACGAUUCCAAAGAGAAAUUCUAAAACUAUUUUGAGAAGCAGCCUCUUGGAAUUAGCGUAGACUUUUCCAAAUAGAUCAUACCCUCCUACAUUUAGAAAUUUGGUAUAUUUUGUAUUUUUUAAAAUAGCUGAUGGUUGCUUUAUAGCUAUGACUUGUCGAAGAUAAUGUAUUUAUUAAAGGGAGAAUAGGUGUGGGACUAUAUGUAACGGUAUUAAAACACAGGCAUAAAGUUGGAGAAGAACUUCAAGCAAACUGAAAAUAUCUUUAGAAAUAUGCAAAUCAAAGAUGCUUUUUAAAUUUCUAUCUUAGCAGAAAAGAUGGUUUUACAAUAAUUCAAAAGCGUAUGUGAACUUUCUAAUGUUAAAUACGACUAUACACAGAAUCAUUUACUCAGAAUUUUUUUAAAUAUUAUUUUUCCCUUUCUUUUCCUCCAUCCUGCCCCUUUUCUUCAGUAUUUCAUAGCCUUAAUUGAACAAGUUAUUUACAGUAGAUAUGAAAAGACAUUAGCUGUCGUAUGAAGAUUUCAAUGUGAAAUAGCCAGCAUUUUCUUCCUGUAAAGUAUUUAAAUAUGUUUUUAAGUAUUUCUUUGUUUGACAGGUGGGUACAUGUCAUUAUUUUGUAAUCAAAGGUGGAAAUAUAUGAGUCAUGUCAGAGCUAAAGAUGUUUUAAUUUUUUCUGCUUCUCAGGGUAUCAUCACAAAUCAGAAGUUUGUAAAUUGUAUAUAUUUUGCUACACUCAAUGUAGUACAAAGUAGAUGAGAUAAUCCCUCCCCUCUAGCCCUUAUUUUAUAAAGCAUAUACAGACUUCAUGCAGCUGGACUAACAAAAACAGGUGUCUGCGGUAUUUGCCUGUUAAAGGCAAAAAAUUGUGUAUUUUUUGGCACCGAGUCACUUUUGGGAUUUAGAGAGAAAUGAUAAAGUCUUCAAUUAUAAAAGACAUCAUAGAAUAGAAGUACAGUUGUGAAUAAAGGGCAGAGGGUUAGAGAUCUUAGAGUAAGGAGGUGAGCGUGUUGCAAAAUAGUGUGUUGCCUGAGAAGAAGAAUUGAAGGAAGGCAUUGAAAAAUAAAUGUGAUAUAGAAUAAACCUACCUGGUGAGUGAAGGGAAAAUCUGAGAGAUUGGAAGUGACAAGGUGAUGGCAUGAAGGACUUUAAGGAAGAAAAGGAAUUCCAGCCCUACCUUUUCGGUGGCAGGAAGUUUUAGGAAAGGCAUGGCUUGUGAAAGAGGCCAUUCUGUUAGUGGCUCCGAGAGUCAUGGUAGGCAAGAAUUGGAGGGGAAAAAGAGAAAAUUGUUCAUAAAUUACUGAACAAUUUACAAUGCUCUAAAUUGUUUGUUUUUAAUCCAAGGCUAUCCAACUAUUUAGUGGUAGAACUAGGAUUUGAACUGCAGUCUGUUUGGCCUCAGAACUCCAUGUUUGUUUCUCUCUAUCCCCACAGAAGUCUACAGGGCAACUUCCUGGGAGCUAAGGCUACUAAAAGGUAGAAGCCACAGUACUCAUCUGCAGAGGGCUUACAGCCUCAGCAAGGACCUUGUGGCUUUGUAACAACAAUCAGCCAUAACAAGUUUACUUGUGGAAAAGAAAAGGUGUAGCACUUUCAGAAGAGGCUAUCAAAGAAAAGAGAUGAACUUGGAAGCAAGAGAUACGCAGCUCAGCAUGACAGAGACUCCAUUCCAGGUGGAAAAAGCACAUGGCUCUUUCUUCUCCGAGAUCCCAGGACUAUCUUAUUUUCCUCAGAGGGGCAGGUUACAAGAACUUCACAUCUCUCAGGCUACAUGUUGCAAAGGUUAAAUUCCAGGUUGUACGAUUUUUCACUUCCACCAUCAAGUUAUGAGUGUGAUUGUUUCCCUGCAGUUUUGCCAAUAGAGUGAUUUUAGACUAUUUACAUCGUGGGUUACAACCAAUGGUAAGUCAUGAAUUUAGCGUAAUGGGUUAUAACCAACAUUUAAAACAAACUGAAGUGGCGUAGGACAGAAUAAAACAUAUCAGAUUUCACCACACAUAGUUUGAUAGUUGUAAAAUUCUUUGAUACUUCUCCCUUCAAAUGAUAUAAACUAAUUUUCUUUCCCCUUAAGUGUGAGCUGUACUUAGUGACUCACUACUUUUGUUUGUUGUUUUUUUUUAACUCAUUAGGGGUUAUUUGUGUCAACAAGUCAAGGAAAGAGCAGCCCAAGAAUACCAUCAGAGAUGCAGCUUUCCAGGCCUCCAUCCUGGACUUGCAGGUUUCAUAUUGACAUAUGUUUGCAAGAUGACUUGCACUUCCAGGUCUCCACUCUCCAUUCCAAGAAAGAGAAAAGGGAGAAUAAGGGCUUUUUCCAAAAAGUUUUGUCUUUCUAAUCAGGAAGACAUGACCUUCCCAGAGAUGUCUGAUUACAUCUUAUUGCCAGAACUAUAUCACAUGGCUAUCCUCAAGUGUUAGGGAGAUUGAAAAACUGAAAGUUUUUAGCAGAGUGCAUUUUCCUUCCCCUAAAUAGUGUUAUGAUGAUCACUUUUGAUGAACAGAAUGUGGCAGAAGUGAAGAUGUCUUAAAUAUUAGGACAAAAAAAGGUAUUGACUGUGGCUUUCUCAUUGCUCUUUCUCAAGUCAGUUAUUCUGGGGAAACCCAACUGCCAUGUUGUGAGGACACUCAAGCAGCCCUAUGGAGGAGCCCACAUGGUGAGGUACUGAGGCCUCUUGCCAACACCCAUAUGAGUGAGCCAUCUUGGAAGCAGCUCCAGCUGACAUCUUAAUUACAACCCCCUGAGAGACCUGUAUCAGAACUACCCAGCUAAUCUGCUCCAAGUUUCUGACUCACAGAAGCUUUGAGAGGAUAAUUGUUUUAAGCUGCUAAAUUUGGAGCUAGCUUGUUACACAACAAUAAUAACUAAUACACUUAGUAGAAAUAAGAAUGGGUUCACGAAACAUUUCAGUUGUAUAUGAGUGUGUGCUAGGUCUCAGUGUAAAAUGAACCCCUUCUUAUAGGUUGCAGUAAAAAACAAAAUGGAAAAUUGUGCACAAAACAAACCAAGCAACAGUUUUCUACUCUGAGGUCUUGCUGCUGCCUUCCUGAGGUCUACAUGGGAAUCAAGACGCAGGUCCUCUUUGCUUUCAGGUGCCCCAAACUUAUUAGUGGCUCAUGCAGCCUUUAUUGCCCCAUCAUUCUAUAGCUAGGCCAGUCACCAAGGGUGGGCAGGGAUACACAGGAUACAAGGACACUUCUCAGAGCUCUAUUUACAUCUAAAUUCUCCUUGAUUUUUUUUUUUUUUGAGAUGGAGUCUCACUCUGUCACCAGGCCGGAGUGCAGUGGUGCGAUCUUGGCUCACCGCAAUCUCCGCCUCCAGGGUUCAAGUGAUUCUCCUGCCUCAGCCUCCCAAGUAGCUGGGACUACAGGCAUGCACCACCAGGCCCGGCUAAUUUUUUGUAUUUUAGUAGAGAUGGGGUUUCACCAUGUUGGCCAGGAUGGUGUCAAUCUCCUGACCACGUGAUCUGCCUGCCUCGGCCUCCCUAAGUGCUGGGAUUACAGGUGUGAGCCACCGCACCCGGCCUCUCCUUGAUUUUCUAAGCUCCUCUCAUCCAACCUGAAAACAUAUUUAUCUAGUCUUUAGGAUAGUCAUUCUGGCUUUUACAGCUUUGUGUGUUCUCUUGGACUUAUUAUCUUGAUUUAAAACCUUCCUAUUUAAAGCAGGGCCAAAAUUUUAACAAACCAAAGACCUCUCUGUUUUUGGCACAGCCUCCUUUAGUACAGAAAAUCCUAAAGGUAAAGGAAGUCCUGUGCGUACAAGGAAAUACAGUGGAAAAAGCCCUCAAAUAAUAUUUGAAAAUGUUAUUCACAUAUUGUCUUUAUUUCAACUCAGAUUCCUUUCUCAUUCCAUUUUUAUCUGGCUCCUACACUCAUUGCUUCACAGAAUUAGUCACAGAAUAGGUCACAAAUGACCUAAAUCCAGUGAAUACUUCUCAGCCAUCUUACUUGACCUUGCCAAACAUAAACCACGUGUAUUAGUCAGGGUUCCCACAAUAGGCUGUCUGCAGGCUGAGGAGCAAGGAGAGCCAGUCCAAGUUCCAAAAUUGAAGAACUUGGACUCCAGUGUUCAAGGGCAGGAAGCAUCCAGCACAGGAGAAAGAUGUAGGCUGGCAGGCUAAGCCAGUCUCUGUUUUCACAUGUUUCUGCCUGCUUAGAUUCUAGCAGUGCUGGCAGCUGAUUCGAUUGUGCCCACCCAGAUUAGGGGUGUGUCUGCCUUUCCUAGCCCACUGACUCAAAUGUUAAUCUCCUGUGGCAACACCCUCAAGACACACCCAAGAUCAAUACUUUGUAUCCUUCAAUCCAAUCAAGUUGAAACUCAAUAUUAAUUAUCACAUCAUAGUUGGCCCCACUUCCCUUUUGGAAAUGUUCUUGUCCUGGUGUUCAUGUUUUUACUCUUUCUUGGUUUUCCGCUAACCACUCUGAUCAUUCCUUCCUAACCUCUUUGACUACUUUCUCUGCUUCCCCAUCUUACAUUUUAAAAAUUACUUUAAAAAUAGAUAAUAUGUACACGAUAUGAAUUUGAAAAGGUACAAAAGGGUACAGAGUGAAAAAUAAAUGUUUUCCUUUUCCUUCCUGCCCUUGACAACUAAAACCUGCCAAUCAUCAAGUCCCUUUUCCCCAAUCUGUUCCUUUUCAACCCCAAAGUCAUUAUCUAGGCCAGCCUCUUAUCACUAAUUUCAAUGGACUUGAUGACGUAGUUCUGGGUUCUCCCUGAGAAACCCACCUUAACAUCCAUCACAAAAUAUUUUGGAGUUCCCAGUUGGUCUUCCACAUGUACUCAAGAAAAUGUCUAUUCCUAUGGUCUCUGUGUUACUCUGCCAGGCACCAUUGUUAAUCCAAGUAGCUCUGCCAAGAACAGUAGCUAUAAGGAAGAAGAGAUUGUGCUUAGUGGACAGCAUUCUUCAAACAUGGCAUCUUUUCAACUUUUUUUUAGUAGGCUUUAUUUUUCAGAGCAUCUUUAGGUUCACAGCAAAAUUGAGUGAAAGUACAGAGAUUUCCCAUUUAUUCUUUGCCCCAACACAAGCAAAACCUCACCUGUUACCAAUAUCCCCCACCAGAGAGGUACAUUUGUUAUAAUCAAUAAACCUACAAUGACACAUUGCUAUCACCCAAAGUCCAUAGUUUACAUUAGGGUUCAUUCACUCUUCGUGUUGUACAUUCUAUGGGUUUUGACAAAUGUCAUAACAUGUAUUUAUAAUUAUAGAAAUAUGUAGAAGAGUUUUAUUGCUCUAAAAUUCCUCUGUGCUCCAUCCAUUCAUCCCUUUCUUCUCCCAGUCUCUUGAAACCACUGCUACUGUUACGGUCUCCAUGGUUUUGCCUUUUCCAGAAUGUCAUAUAGUUGGAAUCAUACCGUAGGAAGCCUUUUCAGAUUGGCUUUUUUCGCUUAGUAAUAUGCAUUUUAGGUUUCUCCAUAGCUUUUCAUGGCUAAAUAGCUCAUUUCCUUUUAGUGCUAAUAUUCCAUUGUCUGGAUGUACCAUAGCUUAUUUAUCUGCUUAUUUACUGAUGGCAUCUUGGUUGCUUCCAAUAUUUUGCAGUUAUUAAUAAAGCUGCUAUAAACAUC